AUGAAUGCCUCUGAAAAUAAUGGCACAGCACCGGUCCAGGCCCCAUUUUCCUCCGCUGACAGCUCAGCAGCGUGCGCUUCCGCUGGAUUCAGGCCAGGACCAGCGAAGCCGCACCUUACACCCACCGAGGAGGAAACAAGCCUGGCCACCCGAGGCUACCCCGCUAGGCCGCGGGUAGUGGGGGAGGGGGCGCUGAGGCAGGAGGUCAGCACCCGGGCGCGGGCUCCCGCCCCACGAAAAGCGCGCGCUCCAAGCCCCGCCGCCGGAGAUGCGGUUCCGGUCCGGACGCCUGCGCACUACGGCUCUCCCCGCAGCCUCUGGCCCUCCUUCCCCCUCCCCCAGUCAGGGCGCACCCUUGCGCCUGCGCUGUGUGUGUUCCUGGUCUGCGGCAGCCAUGCUGAACUCGUAUGGAGAGGCGAGUGGGGGGGACAGAGUCCAGGACCGCGGGAUAGGAAGCUGGGGAUAUGGACAAGCAGCAGCGUUAUAGCGCUCUGGGUUUCGGGACAUAGGCCUGGGCCAUGCGGCCCCCUUGGCCCCUUGGCGCGACCCCCAGGAACGUUCGGAAAGCUGGUCCUCGUGGCUGGGGGAAAGGCGGGGGAUUUGUCCUUCAAACCUUUUACAGCCAAUGGGAGCGUGGAGGGGGGGCGAGCGGGAGAGGGCCAUGGGGGGGGAGGGGAAUGGCCAGCCUCAUGCCUCCGUACCCAUUGGAGGGCAAAGGGGUUAGGGGGCGGUGUGGCCCCCCCUAUUCCAUUCGUCCCCUGGGGGUACAGCAGCCGGGAGCCAGAUUCUUCGCUGCUGCUGCCUUACCGCCGAGAACCACCACCCGCCAGGCGUCUUGCGGCCACACCCCUGGCGGGUUCAGGCAGGCUACGCCCACGCGACCCCUCCCGUUUCCCUGCUUUGGCCAAUGGAGGAGCUACGAAUGGCACGACCUGCUCGAGCUUGGCAGUCUCCAGUUGGGCUGUGCAUGGAAGCUUGGGAAGACUUUGUUGGAAGGGGAGGCGGGGAGAGAGUGCUGGAGGCUCUGGGGCGAUGGCUUCCGCACCUCUUCCAACCACCCUCUUUCCCUGGAGUCGGCGGACCACAGCUCAGCCAAUUGGCUUGGAGAUGUGGCGGGUUGCCACUUCCCUGUGGGUCUCUGCGGCACUCUUCUGCCUGGUGACUGACACCUUGGAAAUGAAGUUUAUGACGUCAUCGUUGCGGCUGGCCAAUAGAAAAAGCUCCCGCGGAGAGGUGUUCCUUCCCCUUCGACUCAGCUUCUUCACCCGCGUGAGCGAGCGCGCGCGCGCGGAGGGGGUGGGGAAAAUCUCAAGCAGGGUGGCGCGCAUGAGCGGCGAAGCUCCUCCUCCCCGCCUAUAUAUAAAGGGCUGGCGCGGGGCUCGGCGGCGCCAUUUCGUGCUGGAGUGGAGCAGCCUCUAGAACGAGCUGGAGGAUUCUGCCUACCGAUACAGAGCCUUCGAGUCGUCCGGGGCCGCCAUUACAAUCCACCUCCAUCCGCUUGGAAAUGGCCUUCGUCCCGGCCUAUGACUGGUCCCAGCGGGCAGUACAGACCCCCUAGAAGCCCCUGGAGCUCCCCUUUUUCGGGCCCCGCCCAAUCCUCGGAGUCUGUCCACCCCCUCUACUCCGCCCUCAAGAGGAUUUCAAAGAUGGAGGCGGCGGCUCCCUAAACCACUUUUCGUGUUCAUCCGCCUCCAUCCGAGAUCGAAACGGGACCUCGUCGGCCCCGUAGGGGCCCGACAAGAAGAGGGAAUCCCUGCAGACCAACAGCGGGCUAUAUUGACGACGGUGUCUGAGAUCGGGGACCGUCUUUUGAAGAGUCAGUCCCUCCUUAGUUGCCCGCCUCAGCUGAGGCCGCCGCCAUUUUCUUGCUGUCCGCCGUCUGCAGAGCGCGCCAAGCUGCCCGGAGCUCUCCGAGAGGCCCCAAAGAGACUGCUUUCGUGCCGGCCAGGCAGGGGGUUUGUCGCCUGGAGGCCCAAGAGGAACGGCCUCCCCCCAACUUAGCGGGUUAUGCUGGACCGGGCGGUGAGGGGAACCGAGGCCACCCGGACUUUCCGCGGCUGAGGGCAGCGCCGGUUCCUUGCGGUCAAGAUGCUGCAAAACGUGACUCCCCACAAUAAGUACGUUUCCGCGAGCCGCGUGUGGGAAGGGGAUGUUGCAGGGCGGCGGCACAGGGGUGUGGGGCGCCGUGUUGGGAGUACUGAGCGGCCCCGGCGCGCUGCUGUUGCGGCGCAGCUGUCGACUCGGUCGCGCGGAGGGAAUUGAGCGACGGUUUUGGAACGGUGGUGGCGGCUCGGCUACUGCUCGUGGAGGGGAAUACAGGUUGUCAAUUUAUACGCUAUUAAUGCCGCCGUGGCCCAGUCUUAACCGAGUCAGGCAGAGCUAGUUUGACGGUGGAGUGGAGUGAGGUUGAACAGCAGGUUUGGCGUUUGGUGGGUCUGGUAUCUAGCGGCGGUCUGUUAGCCUUUUAGGGGGGAUUCACGGACACCUCUAGCGCCCUGUAGGGUUGCCAUGGUGACGGAGCGCUUAAGGGACUGGCAACGGGGAUUCCCAGAGAAGGGUAAAGGGAUCACUCUCCCGUGUGUGCAGGUUCCUAAUGCCCAGGGCAUGUCAUUAAA